CCUUUCGCGUCCCCCACCCUCUCGGCUCCGCCUGGCAGCAGCUCCGCCGCCCAGAGGCGUCCGAGACCCUCCGACUCGUGGGUACGCAUAGGCCUCGCCAGCGAGCCUUGCCCAGGCAACGAGUCGCCAGCCCGCCCCCUCGCCGCGGGCUAGGUCUCACCUCGCCACCAGUACGUCUUGGACAAGUAGUGCCAGGUCUGAUGCCGGGUGUGGUGAGUGCCGCCGGGACCCAGGUGCGCCGCCUCGAUGAGGUCCCGGCGUCGCUCCGGCUGCAGCACCACCUCCAGCUCCGCGAAGGUCUUGCGGUGCCGCUGCCGCCGCUGGUAAUACAGAGUCCCGCCGCGCACCACGUAGCAGGCGGCAGCUUUUCGGAUUUUACGCUUGACAUUGCCCUCGGUGCCCGGCGCAUACGGCUCGCGCUCGUUCGUCAGGUAACGCAGGAUGGCCCGGUAGCUUUCCUCGCUUGACAUCGCGGACCGCGGCUCCCUGAGGGCGCCUGUCAGGGACAGGUGAGGAAAACGGCCCGCUACCUACGGGCGGCUGCAGGAGGAGCGGCGGCACCGUAGGGAGAAACGGCUGCGCCUUUGGCGAGCGCUCUUCGACGGCUCCCUUAGUCCGAAGGAAAAGCGGGCGAGUUGGUAACCAGGGGGAACUGCACUUCUCCAGCGCGCGGGAUCCGCUGGCGACUGACAAAAUGGCUGCUGCACCACCGGAAGUGACGCAAGGCAAGGGCGGGGACUGAGCCCUGAUUGGAGCGCACUCUCGUUUUCUGGCUUGAUGGAGCCGAUCCAGUGACGUCAGGAAUGCGGGUGGACAUUUUGGAAGCGGGUAGGACCCUUCACUGCAGUUCGAGGGAGUCUUUAAGCAGACAUCUUAAGUCCUGGCAGUUUCUCUUUUCAUUUUUCCCUUUUCCACGCUUUCUAAGGAGCCACGUGUAGGGGGAGCUGGUGGACAGUUGAGAGUUCAGCCGAAACAUCCAGAGGGUUAGGAGUCCGUUUUUACGUUUGAGACUCCCAACAUCAUAAAAGCAUAUUUUCAGGCUUCUGGAAAAAUAUUAGUCUCUUGACACGGGACCAGAGACAGCCCAUUUACAUGGAAAUUUAGAUUCCAGUUAACAGUUAUAAAAUUUUCAGUGCCUCCCUCAGUGAUGAGUUAUUGUUUCUAAACUUGCACCUGCUAGCUCCAGACUACUCAAGGAAGAGUCGAGAUUCUUUUGGAAUUAUCAGCAUUUAUAGUCAAUGUUAUUGCGAGUGGAAAAGGGGGUCGGUAACACUAUUUUAAGGCUUUAUUUACAUAUAUUUUUACACAAACGUAGGGGAAAAGGUUCUCCAUUUUGCACCAAAUAUAUAUGAGGGUGCAAGAAGGGGAGCGGACUUGAGCUGCGUCUCCCAGUGCGUGCUGAGGAUGCUAAUACAGGUAUUUAGCUGGUAAUCCCGGAGCAGCGACCCCGGUCACCCUUUCCUGGGACGAAUCUGCAGCGCUCACAGGGGCCCAGGGCUGACAUCCCUCCUCGGGGACUGGGGUUGGACACUGUCGCCGCUUUGCUAAAGCCAGAACAUUUCAGGCCGAGGGCUCCAGCUGCAGACACGGCCUAGUACACUUCUCCACCGGAGGGUCUGUAGUCUCUGGGUGAGGCCCUUUGACGCUCCUAGAAGUAGCUGACGGGCAGACAGGUGAAUACAGUAGGCUCGAAAACAGAAUCAUACAGCCAGCCUCUGGUGUUAGGGGCGUGUUUUUGUGUGUGUGCACACGCAGUAAUUCCCGGAUGGCCCGGACAUCCUUGAAAGAUUCCAGGUCUCCUAUGUUGCCUCAAACAAUCCUCCCACCUUGGCCUCCGGAGGAGCUAGAGUACAGCCGCUGCCACCAAGCCCGGAUUUGCUAUGACACUGAUAUACAAGUUAUAGAGUCCCUGCUUUCAACUGUUUUAGGGUAUAACUUAGAAGUGGAACUGCUGGGAUAAUUUUUAUGUUUACCCUUUUGAGAAAACACCAAAUGAUUUUUCACAGCUGUUGCAUAUUUAGCAAUGCACAAAGGUUCCAAUUUCUCCCCAUCCUCACCAACACCUGUAAUUCCUGUUUUUUUUUUUCCUGAAUAGUCACCCUAAUAGGUGUGUCAUAUCCACUUUUAAGUUUCUCCUUCCUCUGAACUUUCAACAUAUUUUAUGUCUGAUGGCAUUUAUUUCUCACAAUACCUAGAAAAGUCCUUCAUCCAGAAGGUGUUCAGUAAGUAUUCCCAAGCCUCCUGAAUACUAGUCCUACCAUGGCACUCAAACUUUUUCUCAUGUAUAACCCAGCUAAAAGGACACUUAACAAGGACCAGAAAAACCACUGUUUUUCUAGUGAAUGAACUAGUGUAUGGUGGACUGGUUCAUGGUCCACUGGCUAUGUUAGGACUAAUCCUGUAAAUAUUGCAAUCAAAACCAAAUUAUGGUAACUUCUCAAUUUCCUCCCACUGGAAAACUAAGCCCUUCCACCCUGCCCUAUAACGCAAAGGUGCUUAACGUAAUUUAUCUGACUUUAAAAUUUCAACUCGGUAUUGCUACUAGCCUAAAAUAUAUAGAGACAGUUUAUAAUAUCUUUUUCAUUUUGCUGACGCUUUACAGUUUAAGAGCUCUUUCGCAUACAGUCUGAUUUAAUUUUACAGAGCAGAAAACCAACGUUCAGAGAGCUUUGACAACUUAAGAGAUAGCCCCCAACAUCAAGGCGUAUUCCACUUACCGACUGUCCCUUUUUGUGCUUCCUUCUGUAGAGGACAGUCCAGUUUAUCUGCCGAGGAUUCCUCUUGGAAAGGAAAGCCGACUCGCAUUUCGCAUUAAGAAACUGGAAAACCUAGAGUGACAAAUGCAAAGGAAUUACUAUUUAACUAUACAAAGUACAAGAGGCUGAGUAAGCUUGGAAUCCUUAGAAGAUCAAUAUGCUAGUUCUGGCUUAUCAUUUUACAAAACUGAGGCCCACAAGGACCAAAAGGCUGUCACAUAACUGGCAGGUAACUGUGUCACACUAUGAAGGUCCUUGCGUUUAGUCUUUUCUCGAGAGCAGGAAAUCUAGGCUCAUAGCAAAGGACAGGGUGGUGCGUCCUUCUGGGAAGCAUUCUGCUCUUGUCCGUCCCAGGAUUCCAAAGGGUACCUCCGUACCUCAGUUAUUUCCCUUACACCGGGACAUCAGUUACAUAAACCCCUCCUGAUGUCCGACCUGGCUCACAAUAAAUAAUCAACACUGGUUCACUUAGAGGUUUCUGGUCCUAACGACCAGUCCACAGAGCGUCCACGAAGACUUCCAGAGGCCAGUGGUGAUGUGGGGAAUAAACCCGCCUAAACCGAAUUAAACCAGCCUUUCCUCCUCGGAGUACAAGAAGGUAGGUGAAGCCGACGCGGCUUUUUACCUUCCCGUCGGUCCUGGCGUAGCGCCUCCCGUGUCCGGGGUAGAUCUUGUACCCGCUAAAACUGCACAGCUCGACCCUGCAACAAAAAGUGAAAGUCCAUCAGGGAGGGUGUCUACAGCCAUGCCAGGGACGACAGAGAGGAGUUCUGCCCGAGGAUGUAAGCGGAUUGGGAACCACGGGUCGUGCUUACUUCAUGGCGACAGCUCCACGGAAAGACAAAAGAUGGCGAAAAGAAAGAGAGAAUCAUGGGAAGAGACCUUAUAAGGUCGCUGCGGGGAUGGGGGCCGGAAAUCUCCUCCCCAAUAUCCUUCGAUGCUCCUGGCCCUCCUUGAUGACGUAAUCAUCGCGAGGCGAAAGAUCUCGUUUUCCCUGACAGCUGACUUCCUCUGGCGCAAUUCAUCCAGAGGCGCUGGAGGGUUCUCGGGCCCAGAGGGCCUGCCAAAAAGGCAGUCAGACAGUUGGUUUAUGAGUCAUUCUGUCUCUGUCUCUCCUCUCUUUUUUUUUUUUGAGACGGAGUUUCGCUCUUGUUGCCCAGGCUGGAGUGCAGUGGCGCAAUCUCGGCUCACCGUAACCUCCGCCUCCCAGGUUCAAGCGAUUCUCCUGCCUCAGCCUCCCUAGUAGCUGGGAUUACAGGCAUGUGCCACCACGUCCGGCUAAUUUUGUAUUUUUCGUAGAGACGGGGUUUCUCCAUGUUGGUCAGGCUGGUCUCGAACUCCUGACCUCAGGUGGUCCGCCCUCCUCGGCCUCCCAAAGUGUUGGGAUUAUAGGCGGGAGCCACUGCGCCCGGCCCAUUCUGCCUCUCUUACUGCCAAGUAUCCUAGAGCCAUCUUCCGGCUGCAGGGAAUGUGAACUGAAGAGAAAGGUGUCCUCUCUUCUCAUAAAGAGACCCAAAGACGAAUGCCCCGCAGUCUCUCGUUCCACCUUACGAGAAACACCCACAGGUGUGGAGGGGCAACCCACCCCUUCAUCUGGUGCCCAACGUGGAGGCUUUUCUCUAGGGUGAAGGUACGCUCGAGCGUGGUCAUUGAGGACAAGUUGACGAGAGAUCCCGAGUACAUCUACAGUCAGCCUUGCGGUAAGCUUGUGCGCUCGGAAGAAGCUAGGGUGAUAAUGGGGCAAACUAAAAGUAAAACUAAAAGUAAAUAUGCCUCUUAUCUCAGCUUUAUUAAAAUUCUUUUAAAAAGAGGGGGAGUUAGAGUAUCUACAAAAAAUCUAAUCAAGCUAUUUCAAAUAAUAGAACAAUUUUGCCCAUGGUUUCCAGAACAAGGAACUUUAGAUCUAAAAGAUUGGAAAAGAAUUGGCGAGGAACUAAAACAAGCAGGUAGAAAGGGUAAUAUCAUUCCACUUACAGUAUGGAAUGAUUGGGCCAUUAUUAAAGCAGCUUUAGAACCAUUUCAAACAAAAGAAGAUAGCGUUUCAGUUUCUGAUGCCCCUGGAAGCUGUGUAAUAGAUUGUAAUGAAAAGACAGGGAGAAAAUCCCAGAAAGAAACAGAAAGUUUACAUUGCGAAUAUGUAACAGAGCCAGUAAUGGCUCAGUCAACGCAAAAUGUUGACUAUAAUCAAUUACAGGGGGUGAUAUAUCCUGAAACGUUAAAAUUAGAAGGAAAAGGUCCAGAAUUAGUGGGGCCAUCAGAGUCUAAACCACGAGGGCCAAGUCCUCUUCCAGCAGGUCAGGUGCCCGUAACAUUACAACCUCAAACGCAGGUUAAAGAAAAUAAGACCCAACCGCCAGUAGCUUAUCAAUACUGGCCGCCGGCUGAACUUCAGUAUCUGCCACCCCCAGAAAGUCAGUAUGGAUAUCCAGGAAUGCCCCCAGCACUACAGGGCAGGGCGCCAUAUCCUCAGCCGCCCACUGUGAGACUUAAUCCUACAGCAUCACGUAGUGGACAAGGUGGUACACUGCACGCAGUCAUUGAUGAAGCCAGAAAACAGGGAGAUCUUGAGGCAUGGCGGUUCCUGGUAAUUUUACAACUGGUACAGGCCGGGGAAGAGACUCAAGUAGGAGCGCCUGCCCGAGCUGAGACUAGAUGUGAACCUUUCACCAUGAAAAUGUUAAAAGAUAUAAAGGAAGGAGUUAAACAAUAUGGAUCCAACUCCCCUUAUAUAAGAACAUUAUUAGAUUCCAUUGCUCAUGGAAAUAGACUUACUCCUUAUGACUGGGAAAGUUUGGCCAAAUCUUCCCUUUCAUCCUCUCAGUAUCUACAGUUUAAAACCUGGUGGAUUGAUGGAGUACAAGAACAGGUACGAAAAAAUCAGGCUACUAAGCCCACUGUUAAUAUAGACGCAGACCAAUUGUUAGGAACAGGUCCAAAUUGGAGCACCAUUAACCAACAAUCAGUGAUGCAGAAUGAGGCUAUUGAACAAGUAAGGGCUAUUUGCCUCAGGGCCUGGGGAAAAAUUCAGGACCCAGGAACAGCUUUCCCUAUUAAUUCAAUUAGACAAGGCUCUAAAGAGCCAUAUCCUGACUUUGUGGCAAGAUUACAAGAUGCUGCUCAAAAGUCUAUUACAGAUGACAAUGCCCGAAAAGUUAUUGUAGAAUUAAUGGCCUAUGAAAAUGCAAAUCCAGAAUGUCAGUCGGCCAUAAAGCCAUUAAAAGGAAAAGUUCCAGCAGGAGUUGAUGUAAUUACAGAAUAUGUGAAGGCUUGUGAUGGGAUUGGAGGAGCUAUGCAUAAGGCAAUGCUAAUGGCUCAAGCAAUGAGGGGGCUCACUCUAGGAGGACAAGUUAGAACAUUUGGGAAAAAAUGUUAUAAUUGUGGUCAAAUCGGUCAUCUGAAAAGGAGUUGCCCAGUCUUAAAUAAACAGAAUAUAAUAAAUCAAGCUAUUACAGCAAAAAAUAAAAAGCCAUCUGGCCUGUGUCCAAAAUGUGGAAAAGGAAAACAUUGGGCCAAUCAAUGUCAUUCUAAAUUUGAUAAAGAUGGGCAACCAUUGUCGGGAAACAGGAAGAGGGGCCAGCCUCAGGCCCCCCAACAAACUGGGGCAUUCCCAGUUCAACUGUUUGUUCCUCAGGGUUUUCAAGGACAACAACCCCUACAGAAAAUACCACCACUUCAGGGAGUCAGCCAAUUACAACAAUCCAACAGCUGUCCCGCGCCACAGCAGGCAGCGCCACAGUAGAUUUAUGUUCCACCCAAAUGGUCUCUUUACUCCCUGGAGAGCCCCCACAAAAGAUUCCUAGAGGGGUAUAUGGCCCGCUGCCAGAAGGGAGGGUAGGCCUUAUUUUAGGGUGAUCAAGUCUAAAUUUGAAGGGAGUCCAAAUUCAUACUGGGGUAAUUUAUUCAGAUUAUAAAGGGGGAAUUCAGUUAGUGAUCAGCUCCACUGUUCCCUGGAGUGCCAAUCCAGGUGAUAGAAUUGCUCAAUUACUGCUUUUGCCUUAUGUUAAAAUUGGGGAAAACAAAACGGAAAGAACAGGAGGGUUUGGAAGUACCAACCCUGCAGGAAAAGCCACUUAUUGGGCUAAUCAGGUCUCAGAGGAUAGACCCGUGUGUACAGUCACUAUUCAGGGAAAGAGUUUGAAGGAUUAGUGGAUACCCAGGCUGAUGUUUCUAUCAUCGGCAUAGGCACCGCCUCAGAAGUGUAUCAGAGUGCCAUGAUUUUACAUUGUCUAGGAUCUGAUAAUCAAGAAAGUACGGUUCAGCCUAUGAUCACUUCUAUUCCAAUCAAUUUAUGGGGCCGAGACUUGUUACAACAAUGGCAUGCAGAGAUUACUAUCCCAGCCUCCCUAUACAGCCCCAGGAAUCAAAAAAUCAUGACUAAAAUGGGAUAGCUCCCUAAAAAGGGACUAGGAAAGAAUGAAGAUGGCAUUAAAGUCCCAACUGAGGCUGAAAAAAAUCAAAAAAAGAAAAGGAAUAGGGCAUCCUUUUUAGAAGCGGUCACUGUAGAGCCUCCAAAACCCAUUCCAUUAAUUUGGGGGGAAAAAAAAAAACUGUAUGGUAAAUCAGUAGCCGCUUCCAAAACAAAAACUGGAGGCUUUACACUUAUUAGCAAAGAAACAGUUAGAAAAAGGACAUAUUGAGCCUUCAUUUUCGCCUUGGAAUUCUCCUGUUUGUAAUUCAGAAAAAAUCCGGCAGAUGGCGUAUGCUAACUGACUUAAGAGCCAUUAAUGCCAUAAUUCAACCCAUGGGGGCUCUCCCAUCCCGGUUGCCCUCUCCAGCCAUGGUCCCCUUUAAUUAUAAUUGAUCUGAAGGAUUGCUUUUUUACCAUUCCUCUGGCAAAAGAGGAUUUUGAAAAAUUUGCUUUUACUAUACCAGCCUAAAUAAUAAAGAACCAGCCACCAGGUUUCAGUGGAAAGUAUUGCCUCAGGGAAUGCUUAAUAAUUCAACUAUUUGUCAGACUUUCAUAGCUCAAGCUCUGCAACCAGUUAGAGACAAGUUUUCAGACUGUUAUAUCGUUCAUUAUGUUGAUAUUUUGUGUGCUGCAGAAACGAGAGACAAAUUAAUUGACCGUUACACAUUUCUCAGACAGAGGUUGCCAACGCGGGACUGACAAUAGCAUCUGAUAAGAUUCAAACCUCUCCUCCUUUCCAUUACUUGGGAAUGCAGGUAGAGGAAAGGAAAAUUAAACCACAAAAAAUAGAAAUAAGAAAAGACACAUUAAAAACAUUAAAUGAGUUUCAAAAGUUGGUAGGAGAUACUAAUUGGAUUCGGAGAUAUUAAUUGGAUUUGGCCAACUCUAGGCAUUCCUACUUAUGCCAUGUCAAUUUUGUUCUCUUUCUUAAGAGGGGACUUGGAAUUAAAUAGUGAAAGAAUGUUACCUCCAGAGGCAACUAAAGAAAUUAAAUUAAUUGAAGAAAAAAAUUCGGUCAGCACAAGUAAAUAGGAUCACUUGGCCCCACUCCAAAUUUUGAUUUUUGGUACUGCACAUUCUCUAACAGCCAUCAUUGUUCAAAACACAGAUCUUGUGGAUUGGUCCUUCCUUCCUCAUAGUACAAUUAAGACUUUUACAUUGUACUUGGAUCAAAUGGCUACAUUAAUUGGUCAGGGAAGAUUACGAAUAAUAACAUUGUGUGGAAAUGACCCAGAUAAAAUCACUGUUCCUUUCAACAAGCAACAAGUUAGACAAGCCUUUAUCAGUUCUGGUGCAUGGCAGAUUGGUCUUGCUAAUUUUCUGGGAAUUAUUGAUAAUCAUUACCCAAAAACAAAAAUCUUCCAGUUCUUAAAAUUGACUACUUGGAUUCUACCUAAAAUUACCAGACGUGAACCUUUAGAAAAUGCUCUAACAGUAUUUACUGAUGGUUCCAGCAAUGGAAAAGCGGCUUACACAGGGCCGAAAGAACGAGUAAUCAAAACUCCGUAUCAAUCAGCUCAAAGAGCAGAGUUGGUUGCAGUCAUUACAGUGUUACAAGAUUUUGACCAACCUAUCAAUAUUAUAUCAGAUUCUGCAUAUGUAGUACAGGCUACAAGGGAUGUUGAGACAGCUCUAAUUAAAUAUAGCACGGACGAUCAUUUAAACCAGCUAUUCAAUUUAUUACAACAAACUGUAAGAAAAAGAAAUUUCCCAUUUUAUAUUACUCAUAUUCGAGCACACACUAAUUUACCAGGGCCUUUGACUAAAGCAAAUGAACAAGCUGACUUACUGGUAUCAUCUGCAUUCAUAAAAGCACAAGAACUUCUUGCUUUGACUCAUGUAAAUGCAGCAGGAUUAAAAAACAAAUUUGAUGUCACAUGGAAACAGGCAAAAGAUAUUGUACAACAUUGCACCCAGUGUCAAGUCUUACACCUGUCCACUCAAGAGGCAGGAGUUAAUCCCAGAGGUCUGUGUCCUAAUGCGUUAUGGCAAAUGGAUGGCACGCAUGUUCCUUCAUUUGGAAGAUUAUCAUAUGUUCAUGUAACAGUUGAUACUUAUUCACAUUUCAUAUGGGCAACUUGCCAAACAGGAGAAAGUACUUCCCAUGUUAAAAAACAUUUAUUAUCUUGUUUUGCUGUAAUGGGAGUUCCAGAAAAAAUCAAAACUGACAAUGGACCAGGAUAUUGUAGUAAAGCUUUCCAAAAAUUCUUAAGUCAGUGGAAAAUUUCACAUACAACAGGAAUUCCUUAUAAUUCCCAAGGACAGGCCAUAGUUGAAAGAACUAAUAGAACACUCAAAACUCAAUUAGUUAAACAAAAAGAAGGGGGAGACAGUAAGGAGUGUACCACUCCUCAGAUGCAACUUAAUCUAGCACUCUAUACUUUAAAUUUUUUAAACAUUUAUAGAAAUCAGACUACUACUUCUGCAAAACAACAUCUUACUGGUAAAAAGCACAGCCCACAUGAAGGAAAACUAAUUUGGUGGAAAGAUAAUAAAAAUAAGACAUGGGAAAUAGGGAAGGUGAUAACGUGGGGGAGAGGUUUUGCUUGUGUUUCACCAGGAGAAAAUCAGCUUCCUGUUUGGAUACCCACUAGACAUUUGAAGUUCUACAAUGAACCCAUCGGAGAUGCAAAGAAAAGGGCCUCCACAGAGAUGGUAACCCCAGUCACAUGGAUGGAUAAUCCUAUAGAAGUAUAUGUUAAUGAUAGUGUAUGGGUACCUGGCCCCACAGAUGAUCGCUGCCCUGCCAAACCUGAGGAAGAAGGGAUGAUGAUAAAUAUUUCCAUUGUGUAUCGUUAUCCUCCUAUUUGCCUAGGGAGAGCACCAGGAUGUUUAAUGCCUGCAGUCCAAAAUUGGUUGGUAGAAGUACCUACUGUCAGUCCUAACAGUAGAUUCACUUAUCACAUGGUAAGCGGGAUGUCACUCAGGCCACGGGUAAAUUAUUUACAAGACUUUUCUUAUCAAAGAUCAUUAAAAUUUAGACCUAAAGGGAAACCUUGCCCCAAGGAAAUUCCCAAAGAAUCAAAAAAUACAGAAGUUUUAGUUUGGGAAGAAUGUGUGGCCAAUAGUGCGGUGAUAUUACAAAACAAUGAAUUCGGAACUAUUAUAGAUUGGGCACCUCGAGGUCAAUUCUACCACAAUUGCUCAGGACAAACUCAGUCGUGUCCAAGUGCACAAGUGAGUCCAGCUGUUGAUAGCGACUUAACAGAAAGUCUAGACAAACAUAAGCAUAAAAAAUUACAGUCUUUCUACCCUUGGGAAUGGGGAGAAAAAGGAAUCUCUACCCCAAGACCAGAAAUAAUAAGUCCUGUUUCUGGUCCUGAACAUCCAGAAUUAUGGAGGCUUUGGCCUGACACCACAUUAGAAUUUGGUCUGGAAAUCAAACUUUAGAAACAAGAGAUCGUAAGCCAUUUUAUACUAUCGACCUAAAUUCCAGUCUAACGGUUCCUUUACAAAGUUGCGUAAAGCCCUCUUAUAUGCUAGUUGUAGGAAAUAUAGUUAUUAAACCAGACUCCCAAACUAUAACCUGUGAAAAUUGUAGAUUGUUUACUUGCAUUGAUUCAACUUUUAAUUGGCGGCACCGUAUUCUGCUGGUGAGAGCAAGAGAGGGCGUGUGGAUCUCUGUGUCCGUGGACUGACCGUGGGAGGCCUCGCCAUCCAUCCAUAUUUUGACUGAAGUAUUAAAAGGCAUUUUAAAUAGAUCCAAAAGAUUCAUUUUUACCUUAAUUGCAGUGAUUAUGGGAUUAAUUGCAGUCACAGCUACGGCUGCUGUGGCAGGAGUUGCAUUGCACUCUUCUGUUCAGUCGGUAAACUUUGUUAAUGAUUGGCAAAAGAAUUCUACAAGAUUGUGGAAUUCACAAUCUAGUAUUGAUCAAAAAUUGGCAAAUCAAAUUAAUGAUCUUAGACAAACUGUCAUUUGGAUGGGAGACAGACUCAUGAGCUUAGAACAUUGUUUCCAGUUACAGUGUGACUGGAAUACGUCAGAUUUUUGUAUUACACCCCAAAUUUAUAAUGAGUCUGAGCAUCACUGGGACAUGGUUAGACGCCAUCUACAGGGAAGAGAAGAUAAUCUCACUUUAGACAUUUCCAAAUUAAAAUAACAAAUUUUCGAAGCAUCAAAAGCCCAUUUAAAUUUGAUGCCAGGAACUGAGGCAAUUGCAGGAGUUGCUGAUGGCCUCGCAAAUCUUAACCCUGUCACUUGGGUUAAGACCAUCGGAAGUACUAUGAUUAUAAAUCUCAUAUUAAUCCUUGUGUGCCUGUUUUGUCUGUUGUUAGUCUGCAGGUGUACCCAACAGCUCCGAAGAGACAGCGACCAUCGAGAACGGGCCAUGAUGACGAUGGCGGUUUUGUCGAAAAGAAAAGGGGGAAAUGUGGGGAAAAGCAAGAGAGAUCAGAUUGUUACUGUGUCUGUGUAGAAAGAAGUAGACAUAGGAGACUCCAUUUUGUUCUGUACUAAGAAAAAUUCUUCUGCCUUGAGAUUCUGUUAAUCUAUGACCUUACCCCCAACCCCGUGCUCUCUGAAACAGGUGCUGUGUCAAACUCAGGGUUAAAUGGAUUAAGGGUUGUGCAAGAUGUGCUUUGUUAAACAAAUGCUUGAAGGCAGCAUGCUCCUUAAGAGUCAUCACCACUCCCUAAUCUCAAGUACCCAGGGACACAAAAACUGCGGAAGGCCGCAGGGACCUCUGCCUAGGAAAGCCAGGUAUUGUCCAAGGUUUCUCCCCAUGUGAUAGUCUGAAAUAUGGCCUCAUGGGAAGGGAAAGACCUGACCGUCCCCCAGCCCGACACCCGUAAAGGGUCUGUGCUGAGGAGGAUUAGUAUAAGAGGAAGGCAUUCCUCUUGCAGUUGAGACAAGAGGAAGGCAUCUGUCUCCUGCCCGUCCCUGGGCAAUGGAAUGUCUCGGUAUAAAACCCGAUUGUACGUUCCAUCUACUGAGAUAGGAAGAAAACGCCUUAGGGCUGGAGGUGGGACAUGCAGGCAGCAAUACUGCUUUGUAAAGCAUUGAGAUGUUUAUGUGUAUGCAUAUCUAAAAGCACAGCACUUGAUUCUUUACCUUGUCUAUGAUGCAAAGACCUUUGUUCACGUGUUUGUCUGCUGACCCUCUCCCCACUAUUGUCUUGUGACCAUGACACAUCCCCCUCUCAGAGAAACACCCACGAAUGAUCAAUAAAUACUAAGGGAACUCAGAGACGGCGCGGAUCCUCCAUAUGCUGAACGCUGGUUCCCUGGGUCCCCUUAUUUCUUUCUCUAUACUUUGUCUCUGUGUCUUUUUCUUUUCCAAGUCUCUCAUUCCACCUUAAGAGAAACACUCACAGGUGUGGAGGGGCAACCCAUCCCUUCAGAGGUGGGUGGAUCACCUGAGGUCAGGAGUUCAAGACAAGCCUGGCCAACAUGGUGAAACCCCAUCUCUACUAAAAAUACAAAAUUAGCCAGGUGUGGUGGCAGGUGUCUGUAGUCCCAGCUACUUGGGAGGCUGACGAGAAUCGCUUGAACCUGGGAGGGGGAGGUUUCAGUGAGCCGAGAUUGCACCACUGCACUCCAGCCUGGGGGACAGAGUGAAACUCUGUCUCAAAAAAACAACAAAAAACCCCACCUAUAGACAGGACUAGCUACAUAAAUAACUUGCAGGGCUCAGUGUAAAAUGAAAGUGUGAGGUCCCUUUUUCAAAGACGUAGAAGGCCGGGUGCGGUGGCUCAUGCCUGUAAUCCCAGCACUUUGGGAGGCUGAGGCAGGCAGGUUAUGAGGUCAGGAGUUCGAGACAGCCUGACCAAUAUGGUGAAACCCCAUCUCUACUAAAAAUACAAAAAUUAGCUGGGUGUGGUAGCGGGCGCCUGUAGUCCCAGCUACUCAGGAGGCUGAGGCAGAAGAAUUACUUGAACCCAGGAGACGGAGGUUGCAGUGAGCUGAGAUCGUGCCACUGCACUCUCCAGCCUCCUCGGUGACAGAGCGAGACUCUGUCUCAAAAAAAAAAAAAAAAACAGAAAAAGGUGCUAUUAAAGAUACCAAAAUAUAAGGCACUUUCCUUUAUUCUGCAAUCUGUCUCUCCACUUUUCAUAGUAUUUUUUCAUUUGUUAUUUAACAUCAUGUUUUGUCAGGUGAGGACAUUUACUCAGCCAGUGCAGCACUCACUGGUAUCCAGGGGCCAUAGGUGAUUUGACGCACCCACAUGGCCCACCAGCUGUUGAGUUCCACCUCCAGCCAGCCACUGGACCAACAUGCAGUGCCCUGGCUGGGGGCAGGAAAGUCUAACAAACCAUUUCAUUCCACUGUCCUCCUGGCCAAACCCACAGAGGACAGGUAAACCCCCUUGUAUGUGUUUUGUACUUGGAUCUGGGGUGGGCAUCAAGUCACUUGCAGAAUGUAUGAUGGUGCUGCCAGCUUGGGGGAAGGAGGAGGGCAGCAGUAGUAUUGGAGGGGAGGGGAAAGAUAGGCCAUUGUCAGGGAACUGCAGACUCAGCCCGUGGAGGCAGCUGGGGAAGCAGCAGAAAGCGGUACUGCACGUUAGCUGAGACACCAAGCCCUAGGCACAUGCUCUAUUAUUCUCUUGUACUACUUCACUGAUAAAACACAAAAUUAAAGAUAGAAUUAGACUUUCAAGACAGCAACAGCAGAAAAUUAAACCCCAAGUAUGGGACCCUCCUUAGCACAGUGCCGUAUGCAACUGCACUGGUCACACAACUUGAAGCUGGCUCUGCCUUUAGAUUACAAGAAAUUUGGGCAGGGUGUGGCAGUUCAUGCCUGUAAUCCCAGCACUUUGGGAGGACAAAGCCAGAGGAUAGCUUGAGGCCAGGAAUUUGAGACCAGACUGGUCAACCUAGAGAGACUCUGUUUCUACAAAAUCUAAAAAAAAAAUUAGCUGGGCAUGGUGGUGCAUGCCUGCAGUCUCAGCUACUUGGGAGGCUGAGGUGGGAGGAUCGCUUGAUCUCAGGAGUUUGAGGCUGCAGUGACACGUGAUUGUACCACUGCACUCCAGCCUGGGUGACAGAGCAAGAUCCUGUCUCAGAAAAAAAAAAGAAAAAAUUUUAGUGACUUUGUUAACCAGUUACAAUGUAUGGAUUUCAUUUAAGCCCUGCUUAAAUGGACCUGGGGUAAUUAGAGUACUUAUUGGAUUUUUGUUAUUAAGAUUUACUGUUAAUUUUUUAGGUUUUAUGAUUGUACUGUGGUUAUUUUUUAGUUAUUUUUUCAAAGUACAUACUAAAUAUAUUUACAGAUGAAAGAACAUGUCUGAGUCAGGCAUGAUGGCUCACGCUUGUAAUGUCAGCACUUUGGGAGGCUGAGGUGGCUGGAUCACUUCAGGUCAGGAGUCUGAGACCAGCCUGACCAACAUGGUGAAUCCCUGUCUCUACUAAAAAAAUACAAAAUCAGCCAGGUGUGAUGGUGCAUAUCUGUAAUCCCAGCUACUUGGGAGGCUGGGGCAGGAGAAUUGCUUGAACCCAGGAAGUGGAAGUUGCAGUGAGCCGUGAUCACGCCAUUGUACUCCAGCCUGGGCAACAAGAGAAAUUCUGUCUCAAAAAAAAAAAAAAGAAAUAACAUAUUUAAGAUUUGCUUUAAAAUAAUCUGAAGGCAGAGUUAGUGGGUGUGAUAAUUAAUAUUAGAUAUCAAAUUGAUUGGAUUGACAGAUGCCUAGAUGCUGAAUCAUUGUUUCUAGGUGUGUCUGUGAGGGUGUUUCCGGAGGAGAUUUACUUGUGAGUCAGUGGACUGAGAGGGAAGGACUCACCCUGAAGGUGGACAGGCACCAUGCAAUCAGCUGGCCCAACUAGGACAAAGCAGGCAGAAGAAGGGGGAUACUCAGCUCAUACUGCUUUAUUUCUCUUGCUCCCUUCUCGAGUGGGAUGCCAUCUUUCUUCUGCCCUUGCACAUCAUACUCCAGGUUCUUUGGGUUUUGGACUCUGGAACUUGCACCAGCAGCCUCUCGGGGAUUCUCAGGCCUUCAGCCACAGGUUGGGGACUACGCUUUUGUCUUUCCUAGUUCUAAGGCUUUUGGACUGGAAUGAAGCCACCAGCUUUUCUGGUUCUCCAGUUUGUGGACACCCUGUUAGUGAGACUUCUUCACCUUUGUGAUUGUGUAAGCCAAUUCCGCCUAAUAAAAUCUCUAUCUA